ACAGUAGGUAGGAAGUCUCAGAGGAAGGAGCCCCUCCCUGGGAGCCAGACCCCCACACCAUGGCGAGCGUGGUGGUGAAGACGAUCUGGCAGUCCAAAGAGAUCCAUGAGGCCGGGGACACCCCCACGGGGGUGGAGAGCUGCUCCCAGCUAGUCCCAGAGGCUCCCCGGAGGGUGACCAGCCGGGCCAAGGGGAUCCCGAAGAAAAAGAAGGCCGUGUCGUUCCACGGGGUGGAGCCCCAGAUGUCCCAUCAGCCCAUGCACUGGUGCCUGAACCUCAAACGGUCCUCGGCCUGCACCAACGUGUCACUGCUCAACCUGGCCGCCAUGGAGCCCACUGACUCCACGGGGACAGACUCCACAGUGGAAGACCUCAGCGGCCAACUCACACUGGCUGGGCCCCCUGCCUCCCCUACCCUACCCUGGGAUCCGGAUGACGCAGACAUCACGGAAAUCCUGAGUGGGGUCAACAGUGGAUUGGUCCGCGCCAAAGACUCCAUCACCAGCUUGAAGGAAAAGACCAACCGGGUUAACCAGCACGUGCAGUCUCUGCAGAGCGAGUGUUCUGUGCUGAGCGAGAAUCUGGAGAGAAGGCGGCAAGAGGCAGAAGAGUUGGAGGGGUACUGCAUUCAACUCAAGGAGAACUGCUGGAAGGUGACCCGGUCUGUGGAAGAUGCUGAAAUCAAAACCAACGUCUUGAAGCAGAAUUCUGCCCUGCUGGAGGAGAAGCUGCGCUACCUCCAGCAGCAGCUGCAGGAUGAGACGCCGCGACGGCAGGAGGCCGAGCUGCAGGAGCCGGAGGAGAAGCAGGAGCCGGAGGAGAAGCAGGAGCCGGAGGAGAAGCAGAAGCCGGAGGCUGGCCUCUCCUGGAACAGCCUGGGCCCCGCCGCCACGUCCCAGGGCUGCCCCGGCCCGCCAGGGAGUCCCGACAAACCCUCGCGGCCACACGGCCUGGUCCCCGCAGGCUGGGGAAUGGGGCCUCGGGCUGGCGAGGGCCCCUACGUGAGCGAGCAGGAAUUGCAGAAGCUGUUCACCGGCAUCGAAGAGCUGAGGAGAGAGGUGUCCUCACUGACCGCCCGGUGGCAUCAGGAGGAGGGGGCGGUGCAGGAAGCCCUGCGGCUGCUCGGGGGCCUGGGCGGCAGGGUCGACGGCUUCCUAGGCCAGUGGGAGCGGGCACAGCGCGAACAGGCACAGACGGCGCGGGACUUGCAGGAGCUGCGAGGUCGGGCGGAUGAGCUGUGCACCAUGGUGGAGCGGUCAGCAGUGUCUGUGGCUUCACUGAGGAGCGAACUGGAGGGGCUGGGCCCACUGAAACCCAUUCUGGAGGAGUUCGGGCGGCAAUUUCAGAACUCUCGAAGAGGGCCUGACCUCUCCAUGAACCUGGAUCGGUCCCACCAAGGCAACUGUGCCCGCUGUGCCAGCCAGGGGUCGCAGUUGUCUACGGAGUCCCUGCAGCAGCUGCUGGACCGAGCACUGACCUCACUAGUGGACGAGGUGAAGCAGAGGGGCCUGACUCCUGCCUGUCCCAGCUGUCAGAGGCUACACAAGAAGAUUCUGGAGCUGGAGCGCCAGGCCUUAGCCAAACACGUCAGGGCAGAGGCCCUGAGCUCCACCCUUCGGCUGGCCCAAGACGAGGCCCUGCGGGCCAAGAACCUACUGCUGACAGACAAGAUGAAGCCAGAGGAGAAGAUGGCCACUCUGGACCAUCUACACUUGAAGAUGUGCUCCCUCCACGAUCAUCUCAGCAACCUGCCACUUGAGGGGUCCACGGGAACAAUGGGGGGAGGCAGCAGUGCAGGAACCCCCCCAAAACAGGGGGGCUCAGCCCCUGAACAAUAAAUGGCCUCUCAUGCUA